CUCUAUAUAUUUAUUCUUAAUUAUAAUCUUUAUAUAUAUAAAUUAAUAAUUGUGCCAACUUCUUACAAUAAAUCUUGCUCUCUCUCUAUAUAUAUGUAUAUAUAUUGCACAAUUAUGGAGGCUAAGUCCCAAUAUCUACAGUCAGCAAGCCUGAAACCCGGGAGAGCUGGUAGUUUUAGUUGAAAGGCCAACAGGCUUGAGACCCAGGAAAAGCCAAUGUUUCAGUUCAAGUGUGAAGGCAUGAAAGAACUGGUGUCUCAGUUUCAGAUAGUCAAGCAAGAGGAGUUUCUUUUACUAACAGGAAGCUCAGUCUUUUUCUUCUAUUCCGGCCUUCAACUAAUUGGAUGAGGGUGACCCAUAUGAGGGAGGACAAUCUACUUUACUCAGUCUACUGAUUCAAAUGUGAAUCUUAUCCAAAAACAUCCUCACAGGAACAUCCAUAUAAUGUCUGACCAAACCUCAGGGCACUCCAUGGCCCAACAUGUGACAUAAAAUGAAUCAUCACACGUGUAAAACUUUCCUUUUUUUUUAAGGAUAGGAAGAAUAAAAUAUAGAUGGCAGGAGAUUAAUGACAUUUACAGGAGUCUGUCUUGGAAAAUUCACAUCUCUUCUAUGUCCUGUAUUGAAAAUAGAUAAAAGAUGGAGGAAAAUGCUUUAGAGAUUAGACACUUUUAGGUUUUAGAGAGAGAAGAGGGUGGGGUUCAAGCUUGCUAUUGUCUUGAAAGACAAUUUGGAUGGGCAUAGGACUGAAAUUGAGUGGGCUUUCCCCGGCCUGUGCUCCGCUGCCUUUUUUAUUGGAGCUUAAGUAGUAAAACUGGACAACCUGCCUUUCAAUUAUAAGUUGAGUUGGCAGAGAAGCGCUGUCUUCUUCUGUUUUAUUUAGGCAAACCAACUUAAGAAUACCAAACAAUAGUUGAUUAAUUUUCCCCAAGGAUGUCUGUAAAGCAUUUAAUUCAGUUCAGUCAACUUGAGUAACUACCAUGUGCAGUGCACUGAGCUAGGCGUGAUUGCAGGGGACAUGACUCAGAGCAGACACUGGGAGAAAAGGACCUUGUCUUUUUUAAUGCGAAAAUGAAUUUUGGGGCCUAAACUCCAUUUCCAACAUCAUAAAUUACACAUUUCAUACAAGAAGCAACUUUUUGAGAAGCAUAUUUUAUCGCAAAUGAAUAAAUAAUACUAAAAGCAUUUGGAAAAGCAAAUGAUUACUUUUCUGCAACCUUUGAAAGAUUCAGAUGGCACAGACUUCUUAACCUGAGUUGUGUGAAAUGCAGGGUCCUACAUUGUAUUUAAUGCCUUUCUGGACCUAUUUAUGGUGACUUGCCUUCCUGUUGGGGACUUGCAAAUCACUUUUGAAAUAAAAUGUUGCAUUUGUACCUGUAGAAAGAUUGUCAGUGAAGGUUUAUUGCAGAGCUAUUUAUUCCUCCCAGUUAGACAGUGAGUCACACAGGAUUCUUUCAAUGGGGGAUCUGAGAGAACAAUCACUUUUGUCAAAGGGAUGUGCAUCUACUACUGCUCAUCUGCUUCAUAUGAUCUUACCACACUCAUAACAAUUCUGGACCUGUUGCACCAGGAGGGCAACAACAUCCUGAAUUUUAACUCUUCUAGCAGCUCAUCAGCAUCAUUUGCUGGAGUUUUUUUCCUAUAGACCAAAAGAUGUUUUUAGACAUAUUUCAUUCAUAUUUGGGCAAACCACCUAAUUUUCCUGGCCCCUGUUUCCUGAUGUGUAAGAUGAAGGGAGUUAUUUUAGUACUCAUUAACUUCCCUUCCAAUCCUAUGCUAUGAUUUUACAGAUAAUUAAUGACAGCUGUACUUCUAGAUUUCUACUUAGGUCAUAAAUUUUAGCAAUAUAAAAAGAUAUUUGUUUUUUCUUCCAAGCUGUAAAGUAGAAUAUUAAAUAUUUUUGAAAUUUUGCGUUUCUCUCCCUUUAUUCUUCUUCACAGUGAAACAGUGUGAGUUGAAUUAAUAAUUGGAAGAGUGGGUGUCUGCUUGCACAUCAGCAUUCAGUGACCGUUACUUGGGAAUCUAGAUAAUUUUCACUGAGAACCUUUUGCCCUUAAGUCUGUCUCUUUCUUCUUUUUUUUAUAUAUAUAUAUUUUUUAUUAUACUUUAAGUUUUAGGGUACAUGUGGACAACGUGUGGGUUAGUUACAUACGUAUACAUGUGCCAUGUUGGUGUGCUGCACCCAUUAACUCAUCAUUUAACAUUAGGUAUAUCUCCUAAUGCUAUCCCUCCCCCCUCACCCCACCCCACAACAGGCCCUGGUGUGUGAUGUUCCCCUUCCUGUGUCCAUGUGUUCUCAUUGUUCAGUUCCCACCUAUGAGUGAGAACAUACAGUGUUUGGUUUUUUGUCCUUGCGAUAGUUUGCUGGGAAUGAUGGUUUCCAGCUUCAUCCAUGUCCCUACAAAAGACAUAUACUCAUCAUUUUUUAUGGCUGCAUAGUAUUCCAUGGUGUAUAUGUGCCACAUUUUCUUAAUCCAGUCUAUCAUUGUUGGACAUUUGGGUUGGUUCCAAGUCUUUGCUAUUGUGAAUAGUGCCACAAUAAACAUAUGUGUGCAUGUGUCUUUAUAGCAGCAUGAUUUAUAAUCCUUUGGGUAUAUACCCAGUAAUGGGAUUGCUGGGUCAAAUGGUAUUUCUAGUUCUAGAUCCCUGAGGAAUCGCCACACUGACUUCCACAAUGGUUGAACUAGUUUACAGUCCCACCAACAGUGUAAAAGUGUUCCUAUUUCUCCACAUCCUCUCCAGCACCUGUUGUUUCCUGACUUUUUAAUGAUCGCCAUUCUAACUGGUGUGAGAUGAUAUCUCAUAGUGGUUUUGAUUUGCAUUUCUCUGGCCAGUGAUGAUGAGCAUUUUUUCAUGUGUCUUUUGGCUGCAUAAAUGUCUUCUUUUGAGAAGUGUCUGUUCAUAUCCUUUGCCCACUUUUUGAUGGGGUUUUUUUUUCUUGUAAAUUUGUUUGAGUUCAUUGUAGAUUCUGGAUAUUAGCCCUUUGUCAGAUGAGUAGAUUGCAAAAAUUUUCUCCCAUUUUGUAGGUUGCCUGUUCACUCUGAUGGUAGUUUCUUUUGCUGUGCAGAAGCUCUUUAGUUUAAUUAGAUCCCAUUUGUCAAUUUUGGCUUUUGUUGCCAUUGCUUUUGGUGUUUUAGACAUGAAGUCCUUGCCCAUGCCUAUGUCCUGAAUGGUAUUGCCUAGGUUUUCUUCUAGGGUUUUUAUGGUUUCAGGUCUAACAUUUAAGUCUUUAAUCCAUCUUGAAUUAAUUUUUGUAUAAGGUGUAAGGAAGGGAUCCAGUUUCAGUUUUCUACAUAUGGCUAGCCAGUUUUCCCAGCACCAUUUAUUAAAUAGGGAAUCCUUUCCCCAUUUCUUGUUUUUCUCAGGUUUGUCAAAGAUCAGAUGGUUGUUGAUAUGUGGCAUUAUUUCUGAGGGCUCUGUUCUGUUCCAUUGGUCUAUAUCUCUGUUUUGGUACCAGUACCCUGCUGUUUUUGUUACUAUAGCCUUGUAGUAUAGUUUGAAGUCAGGUAGCGUGAUGCCUCCAGCUUUGUUCUUUUGGCUUAGGAUUGACUUGGCAAUGCAGGCUCUUUUUUGAUUCCAUAUAAACUUUAAAGUAGUUUUUUCUAAUUCUGUGAAGAAAGUCAUUGGUAGCUUGAUGGGGAUGGCAUUGAAUCUAUAAAUUACUUUGGGCAGUAUGGCCAUUUUCACAAUAUUGAUUCUUCCUACCUAUGAGCAUGGAAUGUUCUUCCAUUUGUUUGUAUCCUCUUUUAUUUCCUUGAGCAGUGGUUUGUAGUUCUCCUUGAAGAGGUCCUUCACAUCCCUUGUAAGUUGGAUUCCUAGGUAUUUUAUUCUCUUUGAAGCAAUUGUGAAUGGGAGUUCACUCAUGAUUUGGCUCUCUGUUUGUCUGUUAUUGGUGUAUAAGAAUGCUUGUGAUUUUUGCACAUUGAUUUUGUAUCCUGAGACUUUGCUGAAGUUGCCUAUCAGCUUAAGGAGAUUUUGGGCUGAGACGAUGGGGUUUUCUAGAUAUACAAUCAUGUCAUCUGCAAACAGGGACAAUUUGACUUCCUCUUUUCCUAAUUGAAUACCCUUUAUUUCCUUCUCCUGCCUAAUUGCCCUGGCCAGAACUUCCAACACUAUGUUGAAUAGGAGUGGUGAGAGAGGGCAUCCCUGUCUUGUGCCAGUUUUCAAAGGGAAUGCUUCCAGUUUUUGUCCAUUCAGUAUGAUAUUGGUUGUGGGUUUGUCAUAGAUAGCUCUUUUUAUUUUAGAUAUGUCCCAUCAAUACCUAAUUUAUUGAGAGUUUUUAGCAUGAAGCGUUGUUGAAUUUUUUCAAAGGCCUUUUCUGCAUCUAUUGAGAUAAUCGUAUGGUUUUUGUCGUUGGUUCUGUUUGUAUGCUGGACUACAUUUAUUGAUUUGCAUAUGUUGAACCAGCCUUGCAUCCCAGGGAUGAAGCCCACUUGAUCAUGGUGGAUAAGUUUUUUGAUGUGCUGCUGGAUUCGGUUUGCCAGUAUUUUAUUGAGGAUUUUUGCAUCAAUGUUCAUCAGGGAUAUUGGUCUAAAAUUCUCUUUUUUUGUUGUGUCUCUGCCAGGCUUUGGUAUCAGGAUGGUGCUGGCCUCAUAAAAUGAGUUAGGGAGGAUUCCCUCUUUUUCUAUUGACUGGAAUAGUUUCAGAAGGAAUGGUACCAGCUCCUCCUUGUACCUCUGGUAGAAUUCGGCUGUGAAUCCAUCUGGUCCUGGACUUUUUUUGGUUGGUAAGCUAUUAAUUCUUGCCUCAAUUUCAGAGCCUGUUAUUGGUCUAUUCAGAGAUUCAGCUUCUUCCUGGUUUAGUCUUGGGAGGGUGUAUUUGUCGAGGAAUUUAUCCAUUUCUUCUAGAUUUUCUAGUUUAUUUGCAUAGAGGUGUUUAUAGUAUUCUCUGAUCGUAGUUUGUAUUUCUGUGGGGUCAGUGGUGAUAUCCCCUUUAUCACUUUUUAUUGCGUCUAUUUGAUUCUUCUCUCUUUUCUUCCUUUUCUUCUUUAUUAGUCUUGCUGUCUCUUUCUUCUUAUUGUUAGAAUUGUGCUUUUCUGCUGAAUAUACAACGAGCAAGUCUAAGAUAAAGGAGGUGGCCAGGGUCUGUGACUGUUCAGCUCUAUGCAAGGUACAGACCUGAGCCACCUCAUCCUGUAGCAGCCCGUGUGUGUGCCAGCAUUAACAGAAGUACCUUCCAGGGUGGUUUCCUGCAGCUCCACACACGGCUCGGCCUGGACUUGGGAGACCAGUUGCCCCUCAGCUGACUGAACUGUGUGUGCUGGUUCCUCUUCUGGUUUAUAACUGUGCUUUAAUUUUUAUGAAUUGAAACUGUGUCUCAUGCCUGUAAUCCCAGCACUUUGGGAGGCCAGGGCAGGCAGAUCACCUGAGGUCGGGAGUUCGAGACCAGGCUGACCAACAUGGAGAAACCCCAUCUCUACUAAAAAUACAAAAUUAGCAGGGUGUGGUGGCACAUGCCUGUAAUCCCAGCUACUCCGGAGGCUGAGGCAGGAGAAUUGUUUGAACCUGGGAGGCAGAGUUUGCAGUGAGCUGAGAUCAUGCCAUUGCACUCCAGCCUGGGCAACAGAGCAAGAUUCUGUCUUUAAAAAAAAAAAAAAAAAAGAAAAAAGAAACUUUAAAAUGUCAAUGUUUGAGCAGCUAAACAUCCUUGUUCUACAAGUGGAUUCUGAAAUCAUAAGACCUAACCAUGAGUUUGACUCUGCCACUUAAGUCAAUGGCCUCUAACUUUUUUUCUUUUCUAAACAAUGCCGCCUCACUAGCAGUAUAGAAACUGUGAUAAAUGGCCUCAGUUAGUCAUCCUUCCUUUAAAAUUAUACUAGCAACAAUGAAAGGGGCUUUUGUUGGGAAUCUCCAAAAACUUCUAAACCUUGACCCUCCAGGGUCCUGGGAAAAUGAAGAGAUGUAGGAUGUGAAAAGAUGAAGGUGUUUGCUUUAAGAUAGUCAGGUGGAAAUAGGGUUAGAGAAAGUGAUUUGAACCCAGUGGCUUUUCCUCUUUACAAAUGUGUAAACUAAAAUGAUUUGACCAGGUGAGAGACAUUUUCUUGGGAAAUAUUUUCCCAAGAAAAUAUCACUGUUUAAUGAAUUUAAAUCACUGUUUAAAUUCAUAUGAGUUGGUAGCCUGGCAUUGUUAAGCAGAUGACAUUUCGACAGAGUUGCUGUGGGUGGGUCUGGAGUUGCCCUGGGUCCACCUCAAUGCCAUAAGGGAAGAGUGCUUGGAGGCUUUUGGGUGAGGUAUUGUCAGUCACUGGUGGACAUGUGCCUUCUCCAUGGUGCUUGCUCCCAUUGCAGAAGGGUUCAGCCGUGCCGUCGCAGAUGCCAGUGCCCUCAGGGAGGGCAGAUAAAGUGACUGCGUGCAUCAUCUGGGGUAGUGGUGGGGUGGUUCAGACUGUGGCAAACUAGCCCACACAUGCCCCAUCUCUUACCCGGUUAUGAACACACAGAAUUAGCCCAGAAUUAUCAGAGCUUCCAGGUUCCGAUUUUUCAAGCAGGUCUAUUAAUCUGUAUUCAUAUGUGAAAUAUCUAACCUUUAAAUAUUUAAUUUUGUAAAAGACAUCCACUGGGCUUAACCAAAAAUGUCUGUAAGUCACCAGGUUUUUGACUUUGGGUAUCAGAGCUCCUGGGUCUAUCCAAAAGCCAUGAACAUUUACUAUCUGAGUAUAUUUGGCAUAGUCAUUUAAUCUUCCUGAGGCUUAGUUUUUAUUUUUCAGAGUUGAAAUAAUGAUACUUGCUCUAGAAAAUUAUAAGGAUAAAGUCAGAGAGGGAAAAUGGAAAUGAUUUGUAAUUGCAAAGUCUUUUGGUGGUUUAAAAUGUUACAUGCAAGGAUAAAUCAUGCUCAGGUAUGGAGGAGCUUUAGCAGAAACAUCCAUCUGGUUUCUGCUAAAAAAAAAAAAAAAAAAAAAAAUCUUGUUCAGGGUUCUUGUCACAUACUUUACAGAUGUGUUCCACUGGCCGAAAGGUGUACUGCCCUCAAAUGUGCAGCAACCCACCUAACUCCUCCACUGAAAUAUCAAGCUGAGGCUGCUCACCAGCAGCUCCUGUCAUCUUUGACUUUGAAAAAGCAGGUUGUGUCUAGAUUGUGGACCAGCAGGCGUAAGGGCCUGUGUGUGCCUCCAUGUGGGAAUUUAGAGCCAUGGCUCCAGUUCUGGGCUUUGAUGGGGUGGAGAUGGGCCCAUGUCAUGCUGGUUUUCUAUUGUGGAACAUUGACUCAGAAAGCAGGUUGCUUAAAGAAGGAUUAGGAAGAGGACCUGGAGGCUGCAACCUAUAGUCUGUCUUCUCCCUUCAUGCCCUUGUCCAAGCAGCGUAAACCACAAACUCUCCCACUGCCCCAUACACCCCCAAGAUACCAGUAUAUAUACCUCACCCUUUGUGACUGCUUUUCCACAGUUAAAGGAAGACCUCUCUUGAUUUAUGUUGAACCAGGUUUACCCCUGUAAGCGUAGAAUUUUUCUUUGUUGGGAGGAGAAUCAGGAAGGUUUUCAGGGAAUAUGUCUCACUCUGGAUUUUAGAGAAGCCCUGCCAGAUCCCAAACUCAUCAGGCAAGGUUAAUCACCUCCCCUUCCCCCAAAAUUGUGUCCUGCAGUAUCUGGACACAUCUCUGUGAUUUCACUUUUUUGUUUACUGCAGGUGUUUGUCAUCCAUAAUAGACUAAAAUCUUCAAAGGGAGACAGUACAAAUGUUAUUUAUUUUUAAUUCUGCGGCCCAGUAAGCAGCUCAAUAAAUGCUGGUGCAGUUGCACUGAGAGAUGCUGAGCCUUCCAUGUCUUUGAGUCUCAGGAGAAUGUAGAGUGUCUACAAAAGCAUGUGCAUUCCUGUUUAGAGAACUAGAGAGAGGAGGAGGCAAGGAAUAUUACAGCACAAAGUUUCAAAGAAUCUUGCCAAUAAGAUGGUCAAACCAGCUCAAAAAAAUAGAUUUUUCCCUUUUUUAGUGAACUUUUGAAUCAAAAGGAAAUGAUAGGUUUAGUUUGGUAAAAUAAAAGAAGGGGGAAGCUAUAACAAGUCUUUUUAAUGAUGGUGAUGUUGGCCGAAGAAGGGAUUUUUAUGGGAGGCAUCACUCAGUUUUACAAAGGAAGGCAGUGUAGAAGUCACAGUUUGGAAUUUUCUUUGUCUUCCUCAGGAAAAAAGAUGUUCUUGUUAAGCAGUGACUUCUGCCAAUGUCAAGCAGAUAGUUUCUGUUGUUAGGGAAUGCUCGGGUCACUUAAUCAGAUACUCUGCUUCAGCCAAUCAGUACUCAGGAGUAAUGUCAGUGUGCCUUGGAUCUCUGCAGAGCAUGAAUGUGAGGUCAUCGGUACAAAUUAAUAGUUUAUCACGAGGUCCUUGACUUGUACUAUCAUAAAUGUAGAUGAUUGUUAAUGAACAUCUGUACCACUUCCGUCAGCAACCCCACUGAAAACAAAAAAGGUAAUAGCUGGAAACUUCUGAGUCAUAUAAACAUAAAGCUGAUAUAUAGAACUGAGCAUUGUUCUUACAUUCAGUAUAUUGCUGAGCCAGAACAAAACCCCUAAGUUCUUCUUACUUAACUCUUUAAGACUUCUGAGUGGAAUUCAUUUUCCCAGAAGUCCUUUGGUAGCUUUCUAUUGUCUAUACCUGUCAUUAUUAUUAAUUCAAAGCCAUUACAAAUAUCCAGCAGCUCUUACAGGUGCAAAAUCUGUAAUAAUAUAUGUUUUCUAAAAUUCAGAAAUACUUUAUGAAUGAAUAAACUCUGCCAUCUCCAGAAUGGUUUAUCAUAUAACAGUUUUGACUUAAAAAUAAACUUUAAUGCCUCCACUGUAAAAGUGCAGAUAGAUAAAAUAUGCUUUAACAAUAGAAAUGCUUAUUAAGCAAUAAUUUACCAGGUUCUAUAAAAUAACUCGGGUUCAACCUAAUAUUCAGUGUAAGAGAAAGAUAUUUUUUAGGAUGAAAUAAAUGCAAAUCCUAGCAGACUUUGGAUAUGUACUUCAUUAUUUUAUGUAGAAAUUUACAGAUAGUAGGUGCAAAUAUUUCUGCACUAUUGAAAUUAGAUUAAGACUAAAAAUAAACCAUUUUUAAACAUUCAUAAACAGUGAAGAACUGAAAUAAGCCAGUAGCUUCGUUAUUCAUGGGUAUACUGGACAUUUAUACAUGAAUAUAGCUCUGUUUGCUUCAAGGUAACAUUUCACUCUAUGCUGGUAUUUAAUAUGUAAUGGAGAGAGUGAGAGAGUAAGCCUGCCCGUGUGAGGUGCUUGUAAGCCUGUAUUGAGUAUUACCCUUGGGCUUUGGGCUGGAGCGUUCUGGUAGCUACCAACCUUAGGUCAUUUGCUUUAAAUGAAAUACUAGUGCUUGUUGAUGUAGGAAUUGGAAUUAUGGAAAGUAAGAAAACAACAUAAAAAUGAAAUUGAUCUAUUGGAAGCAGGAUGGGUCCUCAACUAGUUGCUCAUAUCUCUUAGCCAUUCUGACUUGAAAUCUUUGUAGUCAUUUUCGAUUCUUGGCAUUAGUUCUCAACCAGUGCAGUUUUGCCUCCCAGGGGACAUCUGGUUAUCCGGAGACAUUUUUUGUUUUCACAAUUGUGGGAGAAAAAGUGGGGAGUGCUGCUGGCAUCUGGCAUCUAGUGAGUAGAAGUCAGGGAUGAUGUUAAACAUCCUAAAAUACACAGGACAGCAUCCACAACAAAGAAUCAUCCGGUCUGAAAUGUUACAGCUGGGAGUCCCUGGAUCAGAAAAAGCUAGCUCCAAGAAAUCACAUUUUGUUUCUUUCAACCUGAAUUACAGAGUAGUCCAGGUUUGUCUUUAACUUAUUCUGCCAUGGAGAUGUGUUUUCAUAUAAACUUGUCUCUUUUUGUGGACUUAUUUAUUUACUUUUAUCAUUUGUGUUUGCUUGCUUUGUUUUUUUCCUGUAAAUGUGAAACAGAUCUAGAGUUUGAUUCUUUGACGAGCGCAACAGGGAAUUGAAAAUCACACAAACAAGAGUGUUUUCUUGGUUGUUUUUGGUUAUAAUAGCUUUCUGUUUUUAGUGAUCAGAAAAGACAGAUCCCUUUGAGUUCUGUUGUGUUAGAGGCAUAAAUGGAUGGCCAUUUUAUUUUAGAUUAGAUGUUCCCAUUCUGGUGGCUUCAUAUUAUAAGUCUGUGAUAAUAAGUGAGUGUUCCUUUACUUUAAAACAUGUUUUUGUUUCUUUGUGCUUGGUUUUUGGACUGCUUAGCAGAACAUUUCAGUUGGCAACUGUAGCUUUUUCUUACAUCUUAUACUUCAACUAUUUUCAAACUGGCAUGCAAUAACAUAAGCAGAAUGAAAUGUAUUAAGUGUGUGUUUAUGUCUAUUGGGAAAUAUGGUGUAAUCUGUAGCUACUUAUUCCUUUUUGUUUUAGCACAAUAUGCCUGUCUCAUUGUACACUGUUCUAGGAGCAAAUAACUAGUUUCCACAAAGAACAAGGAACCUAUCAACAUAGAGGUAAAUUAUUGGCAAUUGACAUUCCUGGCCUUCAAAAAUACAUUCUCCAUUCCCUGCUUUAGUCUGCACUGUGUUUUUUUGUGUUUGAUUUAUAUUUGUAAAUGGUAAGUGAGUUUAGUGAUUCAUUAAAUAAUGUCAAAAGUAAUGGUUGCCAGAGAAUCUCAUUCUUUUUUUUUUUUUUUUUUUUUUUUUUUGAGAUGGAGUUUUGCUCUUGUUGCCCAGGCUGGAGUGCAAUGGCGUGAUCUUGGCUCACUGCAACCUCCACCUCCUGGGUUCAAGCAAUUCUCCUGCCUCAGCUUCCUGAGUAUCUGGGAUUACAGGCAUGAGCCACCAUGCCCAGCUAAUUUUUUGUAGUUUUAGUAGAGGCGGGGUUUCUCCAUGUUGGUCUGGCUAAUCUCAAACUCCUGACCUCAGGUGAUCCACCCGCCUUGGCCUCCCAAACUGCUGGGAUUACGGGCAUGAGCCACUGUGCCUGGCUGAGAAUCUCAUUCUUAAUGUAUCUAUUUUAGCAUUAGGCUGGGUUUAUCCUGAAGCACUUUCCCAGAAUAUGAAGGGAGGUGCCUUAUGAAUCUGAAAAAAGUUUUGUAGUAGAAUGAUAAUAUUCAAGUAGCUAGAGUUUAUUAAUGAGCAAGAAGCUAUAUCUUUGGAAAGUAAGAAUAAUAUUUAUGUUGUUACUGCUCAGCAUAUGGCAAAAUUCACCAAGCAAAGAAGCAGUGGAUAUUAAAGGUUUGCUUAACUUAAUGGCUGGUGUGGAUCACUGACAUUGAAGAUACCUUUAAAAAGAUUGAUUUUUUUUUUUGGUCCUUAAUAACUUGAUGAAACCAUAAAGUUUAGAUGAGGUAGUUGGCCGCCUGAGGUUUGGGUCAUUAGCUUGAAUGAUCAUUCCCAGGUGUUUAUACAUCUCAUUACAACAGUCAUCCACCAUUUUUCUGCUACUCUGAUUAUCUGUUUAUCUGUCUGUCUUUCCCAUUAUUUUGUAGCUGCUCUAAGAGAGGAGGCAUUUUCUGAUCAUCUUUGUAUCCUGGGCAUUCCCUAACACAGUGGUGUGAAUAUAGCAAAGAUUAAAAUUUUUUUAAAGUAAAAGCUGAGUUGAAUUGAAAGAAAAUAGUAUCAAUUAUUUUGCCAUAAAGGCUUUAUUAAACAUGAAGAUUCCAGUGUCCUGAGAUUUUAUGUGAAAUCUUCUGAGAAGCAGCCUGGAUAACAAUGCGUCCUAGGAGCCUGGCUUCAUUUUAAACUGCCUACCAUGAAAUGACUUCUGACAGGCGUGGUUCACUCUUUACGGUCCGGUGACUAGCUGUGUCCCUUCCUGAGAACUCUGGGUCAGCGUGGCCUCUGACAAUGUCAUCCACGUCCUCGUGGCGUUAAUUAUCUACACCAUGGUAUCUGGGUUCUUCAGAGAUUGGCCUCUAUUGUCCCCAGGGGCAGGGGGGCAUUUAUUUUCUUCCCCAUGUGAGUGUGAGCUUCCUGUGAGUGCCACUGUCUUAUCAGAGAAGUCAGGUAAUUAUGGAAAGUGUCUAUGUGACAGAGAGUGACCGCUUUCUAUUUAGCUAGCUGCAUUGCAUCAUCGUUCGUUGCAGCUUCUGGAAGGGAUAUGUUCUGGGGGACACAAUCAUUUUUAAGUAAAUUAAAAUAUAUUCUAGUUGUUUUUGUUCUGAUUCCUAUAAUGAAUCAUUACUAUGUAAUGCAUUUUGUGUGUGUGUGUGUGUGUGUGUGUGUGUGUGUGUGUGUGUGUCUAUUUAUAGAUUAAGGAGGCCUUGAGGUCUAAAGAUACCUUUUGAUCAAAUUUGUGUUCUAAAGUUGUUAAGAAAAAUGAACCCAGAGGGUCUGGAUAAAUAUUUUGCAAAUGUAGUCCAUUGUAUUUGUCUGCCACUGUCCGUCUCCAAGGAACUCUGCCUUCCUGCUUUAAUCUGUGGUCAUGUUUCAUCCAAACCCCAUACAUUAUAAAAAUAAUCAUAGGUUAUUGGGGUUGAUGUCCAUGUUUCCUACCUGUAAUUAUACCCUUGUUAUCUUGUUUGUUAUGAAAAGAUUGUUGCAUAUUGCAGAUUGACAUGGAGCUGUUCUUCUGCAGCACCUGUGGGCUUUGUUCUUUGGAUUCUGGGUCCUUGUUUAUGGGAUGUGUGGUCAUGGAUGUAACACGGGAACACAGGGCUAUGCAGGUGUUUCCCUUGGCUGAUAGGAAGGCUGCAGUUCGUCCACAGAAAUAUAGAUGUUAACUGGCCAUCACCCAUAACAUAAAAUGCUUCUUUAUUAUACUGGGAAAGUGCCUAGAGACAUUCUUGGGAGAAUAGAGAAAUUUCUGCAACUUUCUGCCAAAAACAAUCUUAUACAAAAGAGAUGAGUGGAGAACAGUAUGUAGUUCAUGUUUUGAAAUAACGAAUGUAUUUCUUGAGAUGAGACAUAGCAAUGUAUUGAAAAAAAAAUCCCCUUUCGGCAACAAUUAGGAUGUCGCUCCCAAGAGAGAGAGACAUGAUCUCAAAGAAAAACAGUGGUGCUUGUAUCAUGGCACCAAACAGCAAAAAGACAUUGGGAGUCUGACAGAUAAGCCUUGUGGUUUUGUAUCAAACUGGUGGAUUUUGAAACUUCUGAAUUUCCUUAGAGAAAGUCUCAACACACUAACCCAUAGAUAUGGCCUCAGGUGUGGUUCUGGAACGUGAGUGCACUAAGUGUCUGCAUCAUCCAGUGUGUUUAGUAUUGGAUCCCUCAUGAGAUUUUCAUGACCCCCCGUGAUGCUACAAGGGAUCCAAAACACUUUCAUAACUUGAGCAGGAAAUAGCCCAAUCACCAUGUGUUUAAAAGGAAAGUUGACACAAUUCCAGUCCAUUCUGAAGCAAACACAGGUGUACUAAUUCUGCAAAAUAAAAAUGUUAAACUUCUCCUGUCUCAUCCCAUAGCCCUCCAAAAUAAAAAAGUUUGGUGGCUAAAUUAACUCGAGAUGGAAUAUCUUUGGAUUGGAUAAGUGUUUAUAUAUGGUUUUGUCAUCCAUGACAUGGAACAUUUUGAUGAAAAAUAAAUUAUUGGACUGUUUUAGUCUUUCAUGGAUUCCAAGUGAGCCUGCAUGUUUGCCAUCAAAUAGAUACAUGUAGAUAUACAGCCUUUGCCAACCUGCAUUGCUUUUUAGUGGAUAUUAAUGUGCUAUUUGGGUGAGAUUUAACAGUGUCACGUUCUUUAACUUUCAUCUUUCCAGAUCUCUUGGACUCAGUGCCUUUAGACUUACAGGUUCCUAAACACAGGUGGGAGGUUGACAAGGUAAGGGAGGAAAGCGGUGCUGUUUCUUACCUUCAUGGAAACACGUAGGAAGAGGUUUUCUACCUUCUUGCUUAUGUGUAACCACAUUUAAGACUUACUCCCCCAGGCUGUUUUUGGCCAUAGACAGUGUGGGAAGUGGAUUUCUGGAGGGGAAUUUGAAUGUAUUACUGUUGGGCUCUGUGAAUAAUUGGCAUCCUAGAGGGACCUGGGACGCCAGAUGCUGCUUCUCCCACAGGCCAUAAUUUGUCCAUGAGUAUGUGGCUUUAGAAUAUAGUCCAUAAUUCCUUAUCCAGAAAAUCAGUAUGUCUGAGAUGAAAUAAUGAAAGUUACGAAACACAGAUGCUUCCCUCAACUAAACAAUAUUGCUUUACAAAAGUGCAAGAAAUCAUCUUUCCAAAUAAGAUGAUUCUGGUCUGUUUAUCAUUGUGUGGCAGCAUGUUCUAGUUACUUUUGCCACAUUCCAGACAACCUUAAAAGUUAGUGACUUAAGCAACAGCCAUUGUUUUAUGAUCUCUUUCAGUUCUUGUGGGUCAAGAAUGUGGGAAGGUCUUGGUGGAGUGGAUCUGGGGCCAGUCAGUGGCUGGAGCUGAGAAUGGCAGAACUGGACAGGACCAGCUUUCCCUCUCUUUUGUCCUCCCUGUCUCUCUCUUCCUAGGGUGUCAGGCCUCUCUGUGUGGUCUUUCUGCAUGGGCUACUUGGGCUUCCUCACAGAAUUACUGUCUCAGGGCAGCCAAGCUGCUUACAUGGCAGGAGAAGCUUUCAAGAGUUGCUUAUUCCAGGGAAGCAGCAUUGGCUUUUAUGACAGCCUGGGAGGUCAUGCAGUGUUACUUCUGGGCAUUUUAUUGGUUCCACUAGACUGAAUGUUUGUGUCCCCCCAAUUCAUGUGUUUAAGCUCUAACCCCCAAGAGGAUAAUAAUAGGAGGUGGGGUCUUUGGGAGGUAAUUAGCGUUAAAAAAGUUCAUGCGAGUGUAGCCCCCAUGAUGGAAUCAGUGUCCUUAUGAGGAGACCAGAGCUCCCCUCUCUCUGCCAUGUGAGGAUACAGCAAGAAGAUGGGCCUCUGUAAACCAGGAGGAGGGCUCUCACUAAGAACCUAACCCUACUGGCACCCUGAUCUUUAACUUCCAACCUCCAGCACUACAAGAAAUAAAUGUUUGUUGUUUAAGCCCCCCAGUCUAUGGUAUUUUGUUAUAGCCCAAGUGAAAUAAAGAGGCAAGUUAGAAGUGAGUGAGGAGGCUGCCUGGAUCCAGGGAGGAGAAUCAGACUCCCUCUCUGGAUGGGGGCAUGGCAAGGUCUAGGGGCCAUGUGAUCGUGUGUGGUCAUCUUUGGUCAAUAUGCCAUACACUGGUUUAUAAUUACCUAAAAACAGAGUUUUAGUCUCUGUUCCUGGAUAAGCAAACCAAGAAGCCACUCUCUUUUAGUCUUUAAACAAAUCUUGCACUAUUUGACUCCUUUCUUUUGUAACAGGCAGAUCCACAAGCCAUGCUUGCCUGGGAGAAAAUAUCAAAGGCAACAUGAAAAUUAACCUCUGGGUCCGGGAGUGCUGAAGGUGCCAGAACAGGAAGGGAGGUGGUGAGCCUGAAGAUCUCACAAGCUUCCCUCCUGGUGUGUGUUUCCAGACCGUCAAGGGUCCUGGCUGCUCAUGGUCUAUCUCAGUUGCCCAGGCAAAGGCAGCUCGAGCAUCUCAUCUGACGUGAGUUCAAGUACAGAUCACACGCCCACUAAAGCCCAGAAGAAUGUGGCUACCAGCGAAGACUCCGACCUGAGCAUGCGCACACUGAGCACGCCCAGCCCAGCCCUGAUAUGUCCACCGAAUCUCCCAGGAUUUCAGAAUGGAAGGGGCUCGUCCACCUCCUCGUCCUCCAUCACCGGGGAGACGGUGGCCAUGGUGCACUCCCCGCCCCCGACCCGCCUCACACACCCGCUCAUCCGGCUCGCCUCCAGACCCCAGAAGGAGCAGGCCAGCAUAGACCGGCUCCCGGACCACUCCAUGGUGCAGAUCUUCUCCUUCCUGCCCACCAACCAGCUGUGCCGCUGCGCGCGAGUGUGCCGCCGCUGGUACAACCUGGCCUGGGACCCGCGGCUCUGGAGGACUAUCCGCCUGACGGGCGAGACCAUCAACGUGGACCGCGCCCUCAAGGUGCUGACCCGCAGACUCUGCCAGGACACCCCCAACGUGUGUCUCAUGCUGGAAACCGUAACUGUCAGUGGCUGCAGGCGGCUCACAGACCGAGGGCUGUACACCAUCGCCCAGUGCUGCCCCGAACUGAGGCGACUGGAAGUCUCAGGCUGUUACAAUAUCUCCAACGAGGCCGUCUUUGAUGUGGUGUCCCUCUGCCCUAAUCUGGAGCACCUGGAUGUGUCAGGAUGCUCCAAAGUGACCUGCAUCAGCUUGACCCGGGAGGCCUCCAUUAAACUGUCACCCUUGCAUGGCAAACAGAUUUCCAUCCGCUACCUGGACAUGACGGACUGCUUCGUGCUGGAGGACGAAGGCCUGCACACCAUCGCGGCGCACUGCACGCAGCUCACCCACCUCUACCUGCGCCGCUGCGUCCGCCUGACCGACGAAGGCCUGCGCUACCUGGUGAUCUACUGCGCCUCCAUCAAGGAGCUGAGCGUCAGCGACUGCCGCUUCGUCAGCGACUUCGGCCUGCGGGAGAUCGCCAAGCUGGAGUCCCGCCUGCGGUACCUGAGCAUCGCGCACUGCGGCCGGGUCACCGACGUGGGCAUCCGCUACGUGGCCAAGUACUGCAGCAAGCUGCGCUACCUCAACGCGAGGGGCUGCGAGGGCAUCACGGACCACGGUGUGGAGUACCUCGCCAAGAACUGCACCAAACUCAAAUCCCUGGAUAUCGGCAAAUGCCCUUUGGUAUCCGACACGGGCCUGGAGUGCCUGGCCCUGAACUGCUUCAACCUCAAGCGGCUCAGCCUCAAGUCCUGCGAGAGCAUCACCGGCCAGGGCUUGCAGAUCGUGGCCGCCAACUGCUUUGACCUCCAGACGCUGAAUGUCCAGGACUGCGAGGUCUCCGUGGAGGCCCUGCGCUUUGUCAAACGCCACUGCAAGCGCUGCGUCAUCGAGCACACCAACCCGGCUUUCUUCUGAAGGGACAGAGUUCAUCCGGCGUUGUAUUCACACAAACCUGAACAAAGCAAAUUUUUUUAAAAGCAGCGUAUGUAAGCACCGACACCCACUCAAAACAGCUCUUUCUUCCGGGAAGGUUAUUAGGAAUCUGGCCUUUAUUUUUCCUCAUUUCUCAUGGGCAACAGAGGCCAAAGAAACGAAGCAAGACAAACAGCAAACAGGCAUUUUGGUCAGGUCAUUUGUAGGCAGUUUCUCUUCUCACAAAAGAUGUACUUAAGCAGGCUGAUCGCUGUUCCUUGAGCAAGGCGCUUACUCUCCUCCGCUCAGGCCCCCAAGGCCGCCCUUUCCCUCGCACACAGGCCCCACCCCCACAGUUCCACGCCCCCCCCCCAAGGCCACACCCUCCCUCCCUAGAGCAGCAGCGAGGAUCCAUCAUCAGAAUCACAGUGCUCUCCAGACCUCCUCUCUAAACUGCUUCAUUGACCUAAGUCACUCUCUUCAAUCCCACACCCAUGGACAUUCUUGUCAACUCAAUACCAUAGCACUUUGCAUAGGCAAAAUACUUUUCAGGCCUUUUUAAAAAAUUCAUUACAGCAAACAGCUGGGGAAGGACAUGCAGUCCUCCCCCAGCUCUGUCAAUGACUAUGACCUUGGCCAAAGCACUUCACUGCUCUGGGCUGCAGCUUCCAGCACUGAAUCAGAGGCCACACAGCCCAAAGAUUAGCUUCAUGUCCAUUAUAGCAUUGAGGGAGCAGAGAUACCCAUACACAGAAGCACCUUGGCAUAGAGCACCCAGGCAUCGACCUCUUCCAGGAGAACUGAUUCUGUGGAUGGAUGUGAUUUCAGGAGAUUGUGCAGUGCCAGCAUCAGUGCAUAAAGGGUCCUGUAUGUCCUUUGGCUGCAAAUCACCCACUUCCCUGUGUUUCAGUGGGAGAAUUUCCUCUCCCACCUCCUCACAUCCUCUUUUGCCAGGCUGGAUGCUGUCGUCUCUGUACACAAAUACUUUCUGCAUUCCCCCCUCCACACCAUCCUAGCGAGGCACCAGCACACCUAAUCACAGCAAAGCCCAGAUCCCCCCAUCAGUUGCUUUUACUCAGUGUUUUCAAAUAGGAGUAAAGGCCCUUGCAAUUUUUAAUUAACAAGCAAGGCCCAAGGGAACACAUGUCCUCAAAAGUUUUUCUGAUCCCUCGCCUUGCACACCUGGCAUGCAUCAGGCACAUCUGUCCUACAGCUGGCAGAGACAGAUGCCUCGGUUCUUUGUCAUUCAGAUUGCAUUUGACCUCUUCUCAUCUAUUUAUUUCUUUAUACAUCCAGACUUCAUCACAUGAAGCCUAUUGGGGUUAAGUUUGUAAGUGUUUAAUUGUGCAAAUUGCCACCCUGUGUACCUCCUCCAUGUCUGUCUGCGUGUUUUCCACCAAAGAAUGCAAAGCAGACUUCCAGGUGUUUAAAUUCUGUUCACUCAACAAUGCCAGAUGAAUGGAAGAGGGAACACACUGAGAUGACUUAGACUCUGGUCCACCAACCAGACCCUUGGAAAGGAAUACUAAAAUCAUUACAAGGUAUGGAUUUUAAAUGGAUGAAACUUCAAAUUAUCUUAUUUGGAUAGAAGUCUAUAUUCUAGCCUCAUUUGCAUGAAGUCAGAUAGCCAGAAGAAAUUCCAUUGCUGGUUUUCACGAAAUUCACUUGUCUUUUGCUAAUAAACACAUGGCCCUUUCCCAGAUUAUUCUCUAGCCAAGCCCCACCUUUGUUACGUUGAAAUCCCUCAUUUAUUUUCUUCUCAAAAUGCCCAUUAUCCAAAUGCAGAACCUCUGCAUCUCCAAGCCAGUUAUGCUGAAUUUGUCAAACUUAGACACCCUUGACAACUGCACUCCUACUGUAGGCUCCUGUGCAUACUGUCGUCUUCUGUGGGGGAUGGAGAGGUUAGUGUGAUGAGGUGGUGUCUGCCCAGGAGGUUUCUUUCAAACAUCAUGGCCUCCCAUCCAAUCAACAUCAUCAAAUUACAUGUGUAAUCAAGGCUCUGUGCCAUGGGGGAAAUGAAUCAUUUAGCUAGGCCAGGAUCUAGUGAAAGCCACAGAGUUUAAAACCAUGAAAGAAGUUGAAGGCAGCAUUCCUCAGCUCUGUGACUUGUGACCCUAUUUGAAGUUUCAGGAUUUGGGUGUCACAAAGGAUUGUCCCUAAUCCUUGGCCCUGGGGUCUUCCGAGUGAGCUGGUUUAAUACUCUGAGAAUGAGCAGGGAGAUCCAGAGAAUGAAUCCCUGACCGCAUCACCUAAACUGUCUUCCAAACAUGAGACAAAGCUGACUGUUCACACUGAUUGCCCAGCACAUACCGUCUUGCCAGUUUCUUCUUUUCUCCCAGUCUCCUGUUCAUCCAUUCUGUUCUCCCUUGGGGUGGGAAUCUAUGAUGGAGGUUACUGGGGAAACAGCUCAGCAGAUUUUUGGAGACCAAACCAAAGGUCUCACUAGGAAAUUUAUCUGUUUUAAAACAUUGCUUCCUUCCUGGCUCUGCUAAAUUGAAUGCUCAUUGUUUGUUGUUGUUGUUUUUUAAUUCUAAUGUUCAAAUCACUGCGUGCUGUAUGAAUCUAGAAAGCCUUAAUUUACUACCAAGAAAUAAAGCAAUAUGUUCGUAA